AGUCAGGGUCAAGUGGUGUUAGCAAUCACAUCAGCACCAAAUGGCUCAGGAUGCUCUGGUUUCAAAGCUUAUAAAACAGAGGGUGAUUCCCUUGGGACUCACUCAGCUCGGCUCCGAAAAGCAAAGGCCAGAAGGCAGCAGUGAGCCUGGGUCCCUGCUGUGUAGGGAGACUCAGGGGCUGGGAAGAAGGAUGGAAUCAGAAAUGCUGAAGGUUUACGUGAGCUUUGCACCGAGCGCCUCCGAACCACUGCCUCUGGGCUCAACAGAACACAGGGAUUAAUAUUAAGAUUGGAAGUUUGUGUCUUUUGCUGGAUAUUGGAAAUUGAAUGUAAUGGCAACAGAAUUUAUAAAGAGUUGCUGUGGAGGAUGUUUCUAUGGUGAAACAGAAAAACACAACUUUUCUGUGGAAAGAGAUUUUAAAGCAGCAGUCCCAAAUAGUCAAAAUGCUACUAUCUCUGUACCUCCAUUGACUUCUGUUUCUGUAAAGCCUCAGCUUGGCUGUACUGAGGAUUAUUUGCUUUCCAAAUUACCAUCUGAUGGCAAAGAAGUACCAUUUGUGGUGCCCAAGUUUAAGUUAUCUUACAUUCAACCCAGGACACAAGAAACUCCUUCACAUCUGGAAGAACUUGAAGGAUCUGCCAGAGCAUCUUUUGGAGAUCGAAAGGUAGAACUUUCCAGUUCAUCCCAGCACGGACCUAGCUAUGAUGUGUAUAACCCAUUCUAUAUGUAUCAGCACAUUUCACCUGAUUUGAGUCGACGCUUUCCUCCCCGUUCAGAAGUGAAGAGACUGUAUGGAUCGGUUUGUGAUUUAAGGACGAACAAACUUCCCGGUUCCCCUGGGCUAAGCAAAUCUAUGUUUGAUCUUACAAACUCAUCUCAGCGAUUCAUCCAGAGACAUGAUUCAUUGUCCAGUGUACCCAGUAGUUCUUCUUCAAGGAAAAAUUCUCAGGGGAGUAACAGAAGCCUGGAUACAAUUACUCUAUCAGGAGAUGAAAGGGACUUUGGGAGACUGAAUGUGAAAUUGUUUUAUAAUUCUUCAGUAGAACAGAUCUGGAUCACAGUUUUACAGUGCAGAGAUUUAAGUUGGCCCUCUAGUUAUGGAGACACUCCUACUGUUUCUAUAAAAGGAAUACUUACAUUGCCCAAACCAGUGCAUUUCAAAUCUUCAGCCAAGGAAGGUUCCAACGCUAUUGAAUUUAUGGAAACGUUUGUAUUUGCUAUUAAACUUCAAAAUCUACAAACUGUAAGACUUGUAUUUAAGAUUCAAACCCAGACUCCCAGGAAGAAAACCAUUGGAGAAUGCUCAAUGUCACUCAGAACCCUUAGCACACAGGAAAUGGAUUACUCUUUGGAUAUAACACCACCUUCAAAAAUUUCUGUUUGCCAUGCAGAACUUGAAUUGGGGACUUGUUUUCAAGCAGUAAAUAGCAGAAUUCAGUUACAAAUUCUUGAGGCACGGUACCUUCCAAGCUCAUCAACACCUCUGACUUUGAGUUUUUUCGUGAAGGUGGGAAUGUUUAGCUCGGGAGAGUUGAUUUAUAAGAAAAAGACACGCUUACUGAAGGCCUCCAAUGGAAGAGUCAAGUGGGGAGAGACUAUGAUUUUUCCACUUAUACAGAGUGAAAAAGAAAUUGUUUUUCUCAUUAAGCUUUACAGUCGAAGCUCUGUAAGAAGAAAACACUUUGUGGGCCAGAUUUGGAUAAGUGAAGACAGUAAUAACAUUGAAGCAGUGAACCAGUGGAAAGAGACAGUAAUAAAUCCAGAAAAGGUUGUUAUCAGGUGGCACAAAUUAAAUCCAUCUUGAAGACUUCACACAUUAAUUUGGUGAAGAACUUGACAUUCUUUUAGAAGACUUAUGAUUUCAAUUUGCUACCAAUGAGAAGAGGCAAAUCAACAAAUUUGUCAAUUUAUGGGGGCUAUAAUUAUGGUAUAUAAUGUAUCUGAUAGAAAAUUUGAUAAGAAAAUGUAAUGAAUUUUAUCAGAUAUCCAAAGUAAAGGAAAUGUUUUAAAACUGCAACAAGAGACACAGACAGUAAAAUCAAAGUAUUAUUAGGAUGACUAAAUAAAUUAUAAAGUCUGUGAGAAUAUCAACCAUAGAUAGUUCUUUCUAUAUUAUGUUUUCGCUUUUGUAUUUUAAGCUUUACUUAGAUAUUCAAAACCUGGUAUAUCAAGUCUCUGUUAGUACUAUUGGCAUUUAGAAGACUUUACCAUUAUUUCAGUGCUAGGCAUUAUUGAUUAGGUCUUGGCUCCACUGUUUACCUCUUGCUAUGUAUUUUCUCCCGGUAAAAAUGAAUUGAACCAUUUCAACUAUUUUCUAUAUUUGGAGAAAGUUUGUGCCCUGUGUUUUAUAAUUUUUUUACCCAUAAGACAUCACAUUAUCCCUUUGUAAGCUACUUAUCUCCAAAAAACUUCAGAAAUAGAAAACUACAUUUUGGCAGGAAUAAUUGAAAACACCAGAAGGUUGAAGUUUAAUUGGAAACCCAGAAUAUACAUACUUUGCUGUUUUCUUCCCUCAAAUAUUUUACUAUUUGUUUUAUUUGGAGUUAAAAUAAGAGUAUCAUCCAUAUGGUCCAUCCUAAUUCACAGAAUUAAAUGAGCUUAAAUAGAAAAUUCAGUAUUUUAUGAUAAUCACUUCGUUUUUAGUUUUUAAAAUUUAGAUUAUUCUAUAAUUUACCGUGUUUGAGUAUUUUCUCAUUUUUUUCAUAACCAUACCUGAUUAUACUGUGUAACAAAUAUUUUCUAUUGCAGUUUUCUUUCCAGUACUUAUUAGAACUCAGUAUUUGGAAAUAAUUUCAGCUUAAUUGACCAUAAGAACUGUGGCCAAAAAGAACAGUUUUUUGGAGAGGCAGAUGACAUUAUACCUGAUUUUAGAAAAUCUCACUUUAUUUUUGCUAAUAAGUAGACUAAGUGCUCUGUGUUCUCAGUCUUCCCUUUUUUUCUGCCCCCAUUCUUACUUUGUCCCAGGCAUGCAGAGAAAGAUGGUGAUAUUUUAGGCCAGGAGUAUACCUUGCUAUAACCUAAGCAUGCCUUCUUUAUUCCAGCUCCUAUGUUCUGUGUAUAUCAUUAACAUUUUCCCAAAUAAACACUUAAUUCUCUUUUCCCUAGGUGCCAUCUCCUCAAGCUACAAAAUGUCCACAUCUUAUAUCCCCUUUGCUUCUACUGCUCUGAUUUUGUGGUACCAGUACUCUCUGCCACUGAACAUUUUGAAAUAUUUUUGUUUUAGAUUUGCAAAAAAUGACAUAUAGGUCAGUACUCACAUGGAUUUUUAAGAUAAAUCACCUGUGUGAUAAUAUUUUGAAUCUGAGACGAAUACAACUUUUAAAAAUUGUUUUUAAAAAUAGACUUUUUUUUUUAGAGCAGUUGUAGGUUAACAGAAAAAUUGAGAGGAAGAUAGAGAUUUCCUUUCUCCCCUGACAAAGCCCUCAACAGCCUCCCAGGCUAUCAGUAUCCUGCACCACAAUGGUACAUUUGUUACAAUCAAUGAACCUACUCUGAAACAUCAUUAUCAUCCAAAGUUCAUGGUUUACAUUAGAGUCCCCUCUUGGUGUUAUACAUGCUAGAGGACAAAUAUAUGAUGAUAUGUAUGCAUCAUUAUAAUAUAGUAUAGUUUCGCUGCCCUAAACAUCCUCUGCAAAUGCAACUAUUUUAAUGGGUACCAAAGAAGUAAAUGUAUUUACUGGCUUUUAGAUAAUAAAUAACGGGCUUUAUUGUUUAUUUUAAAAGCUACAAUUUGUUUUAGCUGGUUUCUCUGUUCUAUUAAUGCUUUGAAUUUCCAAAUUUAAUAUAUGUAGUCAUGCAUUUAACUUAAUAUUUAAUUAUUUGAUUUAUUUAAUUUUCUAUAUUCUUACAAUGUAUGUAUGAUGUAUAAUUUAAGGGAAAGCUAUGACUUCUCAGUUUCUUAGAAUCCUAGGUAAAUAAAACAAUAAAAAGAAAACCCUUACAUUUAAAAGAGCUUUCAGGUACAGAAGUAUUGAUACAACUAAGAUCCUAAAUGUUUUAAUUAGUGUUUACUUAAGCCUUUUUCAGGUGAGGAGGUACUAAUGCUGGUUAUUUCCUUGAAGCUUUAUGUGGACCUAUAAAUAAAAAUCCAAUCUCCUGCUAAUAGGUAUGCAUAUUGUGAGAAAAACGUUAGGAGCUGGUAGUAAAAAAUGAGAUUCUAUGCCAAAAUAACUUCUCUUCAUAUUUGCCUAGGCAUUUCUUGACCUUUACCCACUUACGCAAGGAGAAGGAAAUCAUAAUGAUGUCAUGUGAUCAAAGGAAACCAUGGAAGGGUUCACGCUGAUAGCUGAUAGCUUUUACAGUGCUCAUUCCUAACAGUGGAUUUACUUGUAAGCUUUCAGAUCAACACAAAUAGCUGCAGCCUGGGUUAAAAUAUAACAUCACUAUUUGGCUUUUGUUUUGCAUGAUUUUUAAAAGCAGUACUCCUAGGGAAAUGGCCUCUGAAGUAUAUCAGUUUCAUCUCUUACCAAGACUGUUAAGAAGAAACUAGUGGGAUUUUGAACAAGUUAUAUAAUUGUGGUCUGAAAAGACCCUAAACUGAAGUUCUGUUUAAAUAUAGUUACAUGAAUUUCUCUGAUACUAAUGUACUCAACAGCCAGGUAUAAACUAUAUCUCCUAGUAACAUUUUCCAUUUUUGUUUAAUCAAAUACUUGCUUAUGAAGGAUUUCAGAAAUUUGUAAUAAAUGUCAGCUUUUGAUAGCAUAGCAGUAAUUGACAUUUCAAAAAUAUAUAUUUCUUUCUGUGUUUGGUUGGGUGUAAUGAGGAAAAUACCUGAUAAAAUGUCUGAAGACACUUUCUAAUGUUAUCUUGGUGCAUAAGCUGUAAUUUUUAUUCAAAAUUAAAUUUCAAAUGUUUGCAGUUUUGGCUAAAACAUUGAGUUGAAAGAAUUAUGAAAAGUGGGCCCAUAUGAAGUACCAUGUUCAUUUUGAAAUAUAGAUUUAAGAUUUAGAAAUAUAUUAAAAGAGUUAAUGGAGCCUCCUAAAUUGGAUUUUAUUUUGUGGGUGAAGAAUUGUAGGAAGAUGAAUGUGGCCUACAGUUUUAGUAAUCUCCUAGUGGAGUUUUUUUUAACUUAGUACUUUUUUAGUUUUAAGUUUUUUAAUCUAUAAAAAAUGUGAUUUCUAUAAACCAUGAUUACAAUAAAUAAUUAUAUUAAACUGUA